GCUGUUCUCCUAGCAGCGCGGGCCGGUCGGACCGCCAAGGCAGCCGGCGCUGGCGAUGGGAAGCGGCGUGGCCGCCGACACAGGCAGUGGCAAAGUUUCCCAGACGUACACAUCUGGACGCGCGGCUGCCGGCUACCCGUGACCCCUCUAGGAAGGGUUCAGGGAUUUUUAAUUUGGAAAAAAAUCCACCUGGUUUCCUUUGUCAAGGUCUCUCCGGGUGGCCAGCGGCAGGAGCUGCAAACUUGGGCACGGCGGCUACACCGGCAGCGGACCGGGCUUUGGAGAACCUCGGGACUCAGGUGCUGAGGUGCCCAGCGGCUCCGGACGUGCUACGGGGUGCGAGCGCGGGGGAGUUCGGGGCGCACGACAAGGAAGGGCCCCCGGGAGCUCUAUAUGGAGGAAGGAGCCCAGAAUGGUGUGCACCAGGAAGACCAAAACUUUGGUGUCCACUUGCGUGAUCCUGAGCGGCAUGACUAACAUCAUCUGCCUGCUCUACGUGGGCUGGGUCACCAACUACAUCGCCAGCGUGUAUGUGCGGGGGCAGGAGCCGGCGCCCGACAAGAAGCUGGAGGAAGACAAAGGGGACACUCUGAAGAUUAUUGAGCGGCUGGACCACCUGGAGAAUGUCAUCAAGCAGCACAUUCAAGAGGCUCCUGCCAAGCCUGAGGAGGCAGAGGCCGAGCCCUUCACAGACUCCUCUCUGUUUGCACACUGGGGCCAGGAGCUCAGCCCCGAAGGCCGGCGCGUGGCCCUGAAGCAAUUCCAGUACUACGGCUACAACGCCUACCUCAGCGACCGCCUGCCCCUGGACCGGCCCCUGCCUGACCUCAGACCCAGUGGGUGCCGUAACCUCUCAUUUCCUGACAGCCUGCCAGAGGUGAGCAUCGUGUUCAUCUUCGUCAAUGAAGCGCUUUCAGUGCUGCUGCGCUCCAUCCACUCGGCCAUGGAACGCACGCCCCCACAUCUGCUCAAGGAGAUCAUUCUGGUGGAUGACAACAGCAGUAACGAGGAACUGAAGGAGAAGCUGACCGAAUAUGUGGACAAGGUGAACAGCCAGAAGCCAGGCUUCAUCAAAGUCGUGCGUCACAGCAAGCAGGAAGGCCUCAUCCGCUCCAGGGUCAGUGGCUGGAGGGCGGCCACUGCCCCUGUGGUGGCACUCUUUGAUGCCCACGUGGAGUUCAAUGUGGGCUGGGCUGAACCUGUACUCACCCGCAUCAAGGAGAACCGGAAGCGGAUCAUCUCGCCAUCCUUUGAUAACAUCAAAUAUGACAACUUUGAGAUAGAAGAGUACCCGCUGGCUGCCCAGGGCUUUGACUGGGAGCUGUGGUGCCGCUACCUAAAUCCCCCCAAGGCCUGGUGGAAGCUGGAGAACUCCACAGCGCCAAUCAGGAGCCCUGCCCUCAUUGGCUGCUUCAUUGUGGACCGGCAGUACUUCCAGGAGAUCGGCCUGCUGGACGAAGGCAUGGAAGUCUACGGGGGCGAGAAUGUGGAGCUUGGGAUCAGGCACUAUUUACAAUAACAAAGACAUGGAACCAACCCAAAUGCCUGUCAAUGAUAGCCUGGAUAAAGAAAAUGUGGUACAUAUACACCAUGGAAUACUAUGCAGCCAUAAAAAGGAAUGAGAACCCGUCCUUUGUGGGGACAUGGAUGAAGCUGGAAGCCAUCAUCCUCAGCAAACUAACACAGGAACAGAAAACCAAACACCACAUGUUCUCACCCAUAAGUGGAAGUUGAACACUGAGAACACAUGGACACAGAGAAGGGAACAACACACAUGAAGGCCUGUAGGGGGUUGGGGGUUGAGGGAAGGGAACUUAAAGGAUGGGUCCAUAGGUGCAGCAAACCACCAUGGCACAUGUAUACCUAUGGAACAAACCUGCAUGUUCUGCACUCGUAUCCCAUUUUUAGAAGAAAUAAUGAAAAAAAAAUUAAGGAAAAAAGAGAAAAAACUCUUUAUUAUGGACAAUAUCGAAUAUAUACAAAAACAGUGAGAUAGUAAAAUAAAUCCCGUUGCAGUUGUUACCUUGUUUCAGUAUUGUCAACUUAUGGCCAAUUUGGUUUCAUCUUUACCUCUGCCUAAUCCCCCACCUAACUCUAGUUAUUUUGAGGGAAAUCCCAGACAUCAUAUCAUUUCAUCAAAAAUAUUUCAGUAUGUAUCCAAAAUAGAUAAGGACUUUUAAAGAACCAUGGCCACAAUGCUAUUUUCAGUCCUAAAAGAGUUGAAAAGAAUACUGUAAUACUGUCAAAUAUUCUAGUAUACACAUUUUUCUAAUUCUCUCAUAAGUUUUUGUUUUGAUAUACAAUUUCUUUGCUUGAAUCAAGAUUCAGUUGGUUAAUUUGUCUUUCCAGUCUCCAUAAUCUACUGAAUAUCUUUCUCCAUCUCUUUUUCCCCCCCUCUUGUAAUUUCGUUUUUGAAGAGAUCAGGUCAUUUUUCCUGCAGAGAUUCUCACAGUCUAGAUUUUCUUGAUUACAUUCCCCUGAUGUCAUUUAACAGGUCCUUCUGUCCCAUACAUUUCAUCUAAAUUGGUAGUUAAAUCUAGAGACUUAGGCUUAAUUUUGUAGCAAGAAUAUUUCAUAGACAGUAUGUGUGUUCCUCCAUCAUGAGGUACACGAUGUCUACUUGUGUUCCCAUUUGUGAUGCUAACCAUCAUUGCUGAUUAUUGCCUAGAUUCAGUAAUUCCUUAGGGGUUACCAAAUAGUAAUAUUUUAAUUUUAUUUCUCUUUCCUCAUUUAUUAACUGAAAUACUUCUUGUAGAGACAUUUACAAUAAUCCAUUCCUUGGUUGCCCAGAAGUACAAAUAAAUUCAUUUGGAAAAGUCAGGAUAAAUAGUUCUUUCUAUAAUAGCUUUCAAAAUAAUGAAUUGAUUCUCAACCACCCUCCAAAGGGGACCAAUUAGUUUUUUACUAUCCCUGUGAACUUAUGGGUUUAAACAUAUUUGAUGUAUUUCAAUUAAUUAUCCUUACAUACAUUUAAUAUCCUUAUUGACUUGUAAAUUUUCCACCUUUGUCCAUUGGGAGCCUGUUGACAUUUGUCCAUGGGUCCUUUUGACUCUUUAAUGGCUUCCCUGCCAUGAGGAGGGUUCCAGGCUCAUCUUACACAUUUCCUGCUCCAGACUUGUAAUUAGCUACUUCCCUAAGGAACCCAGCUUACUGUGAGUGAGAAAUGGUAUUUAAAACCACAAUCUGGGCACUGGGCAUGCUCAUUGCUACUGGGUUGGUCCAUGUUUCUAGGUCUUUUCAGUAGUCAGAGCUAGAAAUUAUUAUUGUUAUUAUUAUUAUAGAGCUAAAAUAUUUCAGGCAUUCAUGAUGAUCUUUCUCAUUCAAACUUAGGACAACAGAAUUUUACUUCAUCAAUUUUACAUCCAUAUUUCCUUUCUUUCAUGACAAAAUUUCUGGUUCUUAAUGACAACAACAUAGGUACCUGUUUAUUUUAUUCCCCAGAAUGCUCAAGACUGUUUCAGCAUAUUAAUGACAAUGCUACCACCAAUGAUAUGAUAAAUGGUUUAAUUUAUUUUGCAUUUCUUCUUUAGAUUUUAUCCCACUAGGAUGUACAGUCAAAUUCCUAUUAUCCACACUUAUCUAGAAGUGUUCCUCUCUGUACGGUUGUCCUACCAACCUAAGAAGUAUGAUCAGUUGUUUCAUUUUGCUUCUGACUUUUAUAUUUAAAUGUUUAUAGUCAUAUAAAUUUUUAUUUAGUUUAUAAAAAUGAGGUAAAUAUACAGUCCAAAGUCAAAUCUACAAAAUAAGGAACUUUCAGCGUUGUUCUCUUCAUCCUGUUUUCUAUUUCCAAUGUAAACAUUUAUUUUUGUUUGUUUUACUUAAUACUUUGAAAAAAGGCAAGAAAAUGUGAAUAUAUAUUCGCAGGUCCCCUUUCUUAGAUAAAUGGUAGUAUACUAUGCACAUUUUUAUUAUCUCACUUUUUUCUGAAGAUUGUUCUAUAACAGUAUAUAGAGAUAUUCCUCAUUCCUUUCUUACGGUUGCAUACUACUCAAAUGCGUAAACAUUUUAUAGUUUGUUCUACCAAUUUCCUUUUGAGAGCAUAGUGCUAUAAUUAAUAGUCUUUUGCAUACUUUUUUCAUAUUUUUAUUGGUUAUCUUUUGGAUAGAUUCCUAGAAAUGGAAUUGCGAAGUCAAAGGGUAAAUGCAUACGUAACUUUGCUAGACAUCAUCAAAUAUCCCUCCAGAGGGGUAGUAUUUCAGAGGGGUAAUAUUUUUCCCACCAGGAAUGAUGAAGGUGCCUGUCUUCUCACAGCCAUACCAACAAAGUAUGUUGUGGAAUAUUUUUUUUAACCAAUCUGACCGAUGAGAAAGGCCUUUCAGGGUAGUUUUAAUUUGCAUUUCUCUUAUUAAGAACUAGGUUGAAGAGAUUUUCAUAUGAUUAAGGCUAUUUGCAUUUCUUUUUUCUGUAAGCUGUUCGUAUCUUUGGCCCACUUUCCUAUAGGGUUGUUAGUCUUCUCUCUAUUUUUAGAAUAUCUUUACACAUUAGAGAUGGUAAUACUUUGCCCAUCAUACAAAUUGCAAGUAUUUUCUCCCAGUUUAUUACUUGUCUUGAUUUUACUUCUCGUGUUUGUUUGUUUGUUUGUUUUGCCAUCCAAAGGCUGCUUUUUUCGUGUUUUUUCUGUUUAAUGUAAGCAAACUUUUUUUCUUCUUGCUUCCAGAUUUUAAUCAUAGAAAAUCUUACCCACUCUCAGGUUAUAAAGAAAUUCACUUAUGUUUUCUUCUAAUACUUACAUGACUAUAUUUUUUACAUUUUAGUCUCCGAUUCAUUCAGAAUUGAUCCUGCAGUUUGGUGUGAGGAAUGGAUCCAAUGUCUUAUUUUUCUAUAUGGUCAACCAGUUAUCGUAACACCUUCUAUUCAAAAUAAUAUCUUUCCUCACUGUUUUGCAAAACUACCUUUAUUGUACAAUAAAUUGCCACAUACUUUUGGGUCUGUUUCUGGA